AUUCCCUGCCCUGCUGGGGAAGGAGAAGCCCCCAGCUCCCAUCCAGUGCCCCUGGACACAGGUCAGUAGCUGCCCCUUUGGUAUCUGAGCUUCUCUGGGACUCUACCUAGAGGAAAGACAUCAGUGAAUCUGGGAGAGCAUGUGAGAGGCCACCCCAUUGGGCCCGGUGGGUGUCAGGGGCAAGACCAAAGGCUCCUCCGGAGGCUGAGAACAGAGGAAAGAUGACGCCCUAGAGGAGAAGGAAGGAGACCGGGGCUCUCCCCUUGGGAGGGGGCACCAGGAGAGUACCUGGGCAGAGGUGCUUGGAAAAGAGAAUUUAAGGAUCCCAAUACUACCUGGAGGCCCAUUUCUUUGCCUUGUCUUGGAAGUGUAUAGAUGCCCACCCACUCACAACCCCAAAUCAAGGAGCACCCUAUAGAAACUGCCCUGGGCCCAUCCACUUCUUCUCCACCAGUCAGGAUUCUUGCCUUAAUCUCCAGUCUCUUUAUCUUACCUCCUCCCCUCCCCCAGCUCUUGGGUAACUACUGGGAGCACAAGAAAGAGAAAUGGACCCAAAUUCCCUUGGAUGACCCCCUGCCAGGGGAGGCAAGAGGAUUAGGCUGGUGGAUCAGCGGGUGCUAGCCCCUGAUAGACAAAGCCUAGUGACAGGCUGGAGGGGAGGAGGCCAGCCCAGGCCCUGGGGCCUGAGAGGAGUAGGCGGAGUUCAAGGACUGUUUGAGCAUAAAUAUGCCCCCGCCCCCCCAUCCCCUACUCUACCCAUGUCCUCUACACCUGCCAGGAUUCCCUCAUCCCAUCCUCCAGGACCAGACACUUGUGCCCAGAUAGUGCAGCAGGUGACCCAAGCAGCUGGGAGGCAGGGUCAGAGUGCAGAUGGAAGGAUACAGGGCCCCCUCUCACCCACCUUGUCCUUCAAGGUCAGCACAUUCUGAUGCUGUUAGCAAGUGGCUUUAGGAAGCUCUGAGGUCACCACUGUGGGGGCUCCCAACCACCUGGCGGGACUGGCUGGGACUCCCCACUCACCUUUUCCGGGCACCUGAGUAGGAGGGAAGAGACUUAACCCUGUUUAGGCGUGCUUCUGAAACUCAGCUAGAGGCUCUCUAUCCAGGCCCCAGUAGCAAAGCAGGCUUUCACCCCAGAAAGCCAAGCAGAUCUGGGCAGAGAGAAGCCAUGAAGGUUACUGGGAUGUGGGGCAUCACCCAUCCCCUGCCCCCAGGGCCAGGAGCGCCUGGAAUUCCUGGGGAGCAAGUCCCUCCCCUGGCUGGGCAGGUUAGGGAGCCCUUCAUGUGAGCAACAGGAAAUGACAGUGGCUGAAGCAAAGGGGUUGGCUGCCCCACGGGGACAGGGUUCAUUUUAACCCCUGACUCACCCAGCAUGGGUACCUUGAGGAGUGGGCCAAGCUGCAGCCAGGGUAGGAGGCUAGGGACUUGCUCAUAACCAGGCCAGGGACCCAAGGCCCCGAGCUGGGGUAGAUGCUGGUGCCAGGGGACAUGCAGGGGCUUGGCACAGUGGGUGAAAUGGAGGCUUCCUGGACCAUCUCUCGGCCUAUCAGUAUUGUUCUGGGGCUCGAGUUGCACCUGGCUUCACUUUCAUUCACCUGCAGUGGAAAAUCCAGAGGGCUGCUCCUGCCAGAGUCUGUACACCGCAUGCUGUUACUGGAUGACGGACACCUGGAUCCUGUGGUGGUCCUUCCCUCAAACCCCACCCACAGGUCCCAGUCCUGACCCGUCCCAUGGAGAGCCAGGGAAGAGUGAAGCAGGGGUCUGGGCUUCAGGCCAGAUAUAGCAGACAGAGCACGAGUCCAGCCCAGCUCUGCCACUGCUCCCAGUGUGACUUUGGGAAAUCCACAUCACUCCCAGCAUCGCCAACUUCCUCAUCUGCAAAUGGACGUGAUAACAGCACCUACCGCUUAAAGGAGCAGGGAGGAUUCAGUGAGUUAAUGCACUGUGUCCCAAGCCUUAGUGCAGUUUUAAGCUUUAAUAACUUCAGAAAUAUGAAUGCUAAAAACUUCAUUUGAAAGUUUCCAUAUUUAAAUUUCUUGUAUAUUUAUUUUUUAAUUGUGAAAAUGUUUUUAAAUUUUAAUUUAAAUAAUUUAAUCUGUCCAAAGAGGUGUGUAAGUUGGAGACAUUUAUGUCUGAAAGAAUCCCAGCUUAAACCUGCACUAAGACUUUUUGGGGUGCUCUGUGUAUGAAGCACAUCUAGAAGAAUGCGUCACAUGGCAAGGGCCGAUGAGAGCUGAUGUGAGACUGCAGAGAAGAUGGACUCAGAAGCUGCAUGUGAAGUACUCAACAUGCCUGGGGCCUGGUUCAGAGGUGAUCAGCACCAGCCAGCUGGGGUGACAGCUGCUUGGCUCAGAUGCCCUGACAGGAAGCCCAGUGCCUCUGUGCAGAGGAACUCUGCUGCACCUCCCAGGAGAGGGAAACUGAGCAAAGCAACAGGAAUCUCUGACAGAGAAGGAAGGGUCAGGACACCUCAGUGAAGAUGGCCAGGAGGAGGAGCUGGGCAGGGGACUGCCCCCAUUGUCCAAGGUGGCGGACACCUGGAGAGGCGCUGCCUGGAGCUGCAUGCCUGUACUUGCCAGCUCUGGGUAAACAGUGAAAGGAGCUGGGCAGCAGGGGCCCCCCGCACUGGGCAGGGAGGGGUAUGGGGGAUCCCAGCCAAUUGGCUUGCCUCCCACUGCCCCAUGAAAGGGCCAUUCAGUUCAGGCUGUUCCUGUGGCAACAGGGAGACUCGCAGCCACGUGAGUGCCCGUCCUGUCCCUGUCUUGCGCAGCGAGACUCCGGCCAGGGCCCCAGCCCGCUCUCCUGCCCAUAGUGCAUUCUGUGGCCUCCAGGGACAGCUGUGCAGCCCAUGAGGCUCCCAGUCCCCACUGAGUGCCACCCUGAAGGAUGUCCCAGCUCUCCUCCACCCUGAAGCGCUACACAGAAUCGGCCCGCUACACAGAUGCCCACUAUGCCAAGUCGGGCUAUGGUGCCUACACCCCGUCCUCCUAUGGGGCCAAUCUGGCUGCCUCCUUACUGGAGAAGGAGAAACUUGGUUUCAAGCCGGUCCCCACCAGCAGCUUCCUCACCCGUCCCCGUACCUAUGGCCCCUCCUCCCUCCUGGACUAUGACCGGGGCCGCCCCCUGCUGAGACCCGACAUCACUGGGGGUGGUAAGCGGGCAGAGAGCCAGACCCGGGGUACUGAGCGGCCUUUAGGCAGUGGCCUCAGCGGGGGCAGCGGAUUCCCUUAUGGAGUGACCAACAACUGCCUCAGCUACCUGCCCAUCAAUGCCUAUGACCAGGGGGUGACCCUAACCCAGAAGCUGGACAGCCAAUCAGACCUGGCCCGGGAUUUCUCCAGCCUCCGGACCUCAGAUAGCUACCGGAUAGACCCCAGGAACCUGGGCCGCAGCCCCAUGCUGGCCCGGACGCGCAAGGAGCUCUGCACCCUGCAGGGGCUCUACCAGACAGCCAGCUGCCCUGAAUACCUGGUCGACUACCUGGAGAACUAUGGUCGCAAGGGCAGUGCAUCUCAGGUGCCCUCCCAGGCCCCUCCCUCACGAGUCCCUGAAAUCAUCAGCCCAACCUACCGACCCAUUGGCCGCUACACGCUGUGGGAGACGGGAAAGGGUCAGGCCCCUGGGCCCAGCCGCUCCAGCUCCCCGGGAAGAGACGGCAUGAAUUCUAAGAGUGCCCAGGGUCUGGCUGGUCUUCGAAACCUUGGGAACACGUGCUUCAUGAACUCAAUUCUGCAGUGCCUGAGCAACACUCGGGAGUUGAGAGAUUACUGCCUCCAGAGGCUCUACAUGCGGGACCUGCACCACGGCAGCAAUGCACACACAGCCCUCGUGGAAGAGUUUGCAAAACUAAUUCAGACCAUAUGGACUUCAUCCCCCAAUGAUGUGGUGAGCCCAUCUGAGUUCAAGACCCAGAUCCAGAGAUACGCACCGCGCUUUGUUGGCUAUAAUCAGCAGGAUGCUCAGGAGUUCCUUCGCUUUCUUCUGGAUGGGCUCCAUAACGAGGUGAACCGAGUGACACUGAGACCUAAGUCCAACCCUGAGAACCUCGAUCAUCUUCCUGAUGACGAGAAAGGCCGACAGAUGUGGAGAAAAUAUCUAGAACGGGAAGACAGUAGGAUCGGGGAUCUCUUUGUUGGGCAGCUAAAGAGCUCGCUGACGUGUACAGAUUGUGGUUACUGUUCUACGGUCUUCGACCCCUUCUGGGACCUCUCACUGCCCAUUGCUAAGCGAGGUUAUCCUGAGGUGACAUUAAUGGACUGCAUGAGGCUCUUCACCAAAGAGGAUGUGCUUGAUGGAGAUGAAAAGCCAACAUGCUGUCGCUGCCGAGGCAGAAAACGGUGUAUAAAGAAGUUCUCCAUCCAGAGGUUCCCAAAGAUCUUGGUGCUCCAUCUGAAGCGGUUCUCAGAAUCCAGGAUCCGAACCAGCAAGCUCACAACAUUUGUGAACUUCCCCCUAAGAGACCUGGACUUAAGAGAAUUUGCCUCAGAAAACACCAACCAUGCUGUUUACAACCUGUACGCUGUGUCCAAUCACUCCGGAACCACCAUGGGUGGCCACUAUACAGCCUACUGUCGCAGUCCAGGGACAGGAGAAUGGCACACUUUCAACGACUCCAGCGUCACUCCCAUGUCCUCCAGCCAAGUGCGCACCAGCGACGCCUACCUGCUCUUCUACGAACUGGCCAGCCCGCCCUCCCGAAUGUAGCGCCAGGAGCCACGUCCCUUCUCCCUUCCCCGUGGUGGCCCCGCUCCCUAAAUUUUUUAAAAAGACAAAAACAAAACAACAACAACAACACACAAACCUGACAAGAGAAAAACAAACCUGAAGCUGCCGAGCAGGAGUGGAUGCAGCCUGAUCAGGGUCUGGAGCAAGGAGCCGGGCUUUCCUGAGCUGUGGCCCGGCAGGGAAGAUCGCCUGGACGUGGAGCCAGCAUCGCCCCGUGCCCUCGGCGUUUGCAUUUGUAAACUUGUGGUCUUCCUAUGUGUCAGAAACAACUGUGUCUUGGGGGGGAAGACCCUCGCUGCGCCGCUUCCCGCCGCAGCGCCCGCGCCUCCGAGGGGACAGCGCCCUCUGGAGCUCGCUGGGAGCAUCACCGCCUGGACGCCCGCGCCGCGGAGGAGCCGGCGCCCAUCUCCACCCGCACGGCUCGCCGGUCCAGAGCCAUGAGCCAAGAGCCCUCUUCACGCUGCUAACUCCAGGGGACAGACGAAGGGACAUCUUUGGAAAACGCUGGUUUUGGUUUUUAAAAAGCCCAACUUUUUUUUUUUAAUUUCCAUAACUAAAGUGUUCAGACUGGAGUGCUCUCCUUCAGGCCUCUUCAUAGCUGGGACGUUGCACUGGUCCUUUUAUUGCUUUUCCAAGUACAACUUUCUAAUGCUAGCCCUCCGUGGUGCUAGGUGGGCGUUGGCCAGGCCCCAAGCACAGCCACAGUAGACCUGGGAUCUAAAACAAGUUUCUGUUUUGGGGGUUUGGGUUUUUUUUUUUUUUUUUUAAUGUUUUGAAUGGAAUUUAGUUGCCUCCAAGAAUUGUGCCUUAUAGCAUUUGGGGACCAGGGGGUAACUGCCCCUCCUGAAAUAUCCCUCAGCCUCUUCCCUUUUCCCCAGUGCUCUGUUCAAACCCGCCUGGGAAAGGGAUCCUGCCCUUAGCCCUGGCUCGUUGUGCAUUGCAGUGAGGCAAAGAAGAAAGCAGGUAGAUUCCUUCCGACAGGGCAUCAAGUUCUUCCCGCCCACGUCCUCUAGCCCACCCCUGGUCUGCUCCCCAGCUGUUUGAAGGAUAGCACAAGCCCCUCGUCCCUAGAGCUUCUCUCCCUUUUAUUUAUUCUCUUAACAUCCCUUUCCCCCUGGCCUUCCUGCCCCCGCCCCCUUCUCAGAGCCUCCUAGACAAUAGGCCCUUUGGACCGAGUUUCUCAGGGAUGCCCAGGCCACCCCUCAGCUCUUCUUAGCGCUGGUCUCCAGUCCUGCCCUGGGAGCUGGAGCCUGGGUAUUUGGGGACAUCUUGCCUCAGUUGUAUGGUUCUUUCCUGUGGGCUCAAUUUUGCCCUACAUAGUUGGAUAAAACUCUGUGCUGUCCUGGAGAGUAAAGCUGUUCACCCACACAGCUGGGCCCGGCUUGUGCCCCGUGGAGCCUGGCACAUUCCAGGCUCCUAGGAGGAGGCAUCAGAGAAAGACACCCUGAGUUUUACUGGCCUGACACCCUUCUCCAGAGAAGACCUGUGAACCUGAGCCCAAGGGCAAGUGUACACUUGUUUACUGUGUAAGCAAGAGUAGAAGAAUGUCUAAUGUACAGUGGAACCUUGUACAGAAUAAAUAAUAGCUUUGAGAAAUCA